CCCUCUUCUCUCGCCGCCUCCUGGCCUCCGCACCGACGCGGCCCGGGCUGGAGCCGAGCCGGGGCCGAGCUGCAGGCCGGACCGGAGCCGGAUCUGUACCCGCUGAGACGUGGAAACAUGGAGGCCUGAGCCGGUGUGCGCCACCUGGGCUGCGGCGGCGACAGCGACUUCUCCUGACCCCUCUGCCACCCUCCCAUCCGUCCGCGGGUCCGUGGAGCUGGAGCAGAUCCCCCAGCCGGCUGAGACAGGCCUACUAUAGGAAACGUUGCUUAUCUUUCAAUUUCUUUGCUGCCUGCUCUUCAGCUGUAAUUAGGGUUUGGCUUAGAAGCAACAUAAAAUCUCUUCAUGAGAGGUGAAACACCUGAGUUAAAUUUUGGAAAGCUUCUAUAUACCUAUCAGGGUCUUCAGAAAAUUGGCCUCAGUCACCUUUAUUUGCCUAAGGUCUUGCAAAGAGGAGGGAACUUGAACCCUAGUGACAUCACCUCCAUUGGGCAUUUCCUGUAGAGGUUGUCUUUUGGAAAUGCAGGUUUAAGGACAAAUUAUCUGCUUAAGCUAGAAGAUGGGAUCGAAUAGCAGCAGAAUCGGCGAUCUUCCUAAAAAUGAGUACUUGAAAAAGUUAUCAGGCACGGAAUCUAUCUCUGAGAAUGACCCGUUCUGGAAUCAGCUUCUCUCAUUUUCUUUCCCUGCACCAACUAGCAGUAGUGAGUUGAAACUCUUGGAGGAAGCAACCAUUUCAGUCUGCAGGUCAUUAGUUGAAAACAAUCCUCGAACAGGAAAUCUUGGUGCACUAAUUAAGGUCUUCCUUUCUAGAACCAAAGAACUAAAACUUUCAGCAGAAUGUCAGAACCACAUCUUCAUUUGGCAGACACACAAUGCUUUGUUUAUUAUUUGCUGUUUGCUGAAAGUGUUCAUCUGUCAGAUGUCAGAGGAGGAAUUACAACUUCAUUUUACUUAUGAAGAAAAAUCUCCUGGCAAUUACAGUUCUGACUCAGAAGAUCUUUUGGAAGAAUUGCUGUGCUGUUUGAUGCAGUUGAUCACUGAUAUUCCACUCUUAGAUAUUACAUAUGAAAUAUCAGUAGAAGCUAUAUCAACAAUGGUUGUUUUCCUUUCCUGCCAACUCUUCCACAAAGAAGUUUUGCGACAGAGCAUCAGCCACAAGUAUUUGAUGCGAGGUCCAUGUCUUCCAUACACCAGCAAACUUGUGAAGACCUUAUUAUAUAACUUUAUCAGACAAGAAAAGCCACCUCCUCCAGGGGCCCAUGUUUUCCCUCAGCAGUCGGAUGGGGGAGGACUGCUUUAUGGACUUGCAUCAGGAGUAGCAACAGGACUCUGGACUGUCUUCACACUAGGUGGUGUGGGCAGCAAAGCGGCUGCCUCUCCAGAGCUUUCUUCCCCUCUGGCCAACCAGAGUCUCCUGCUUCUGCUGGUGUUGGCCAAUCUGACAGAUGCCUCAGAUGCGCCAAACCCCUACAGACAAGCCAUUAUGUCCUUCAAGAACACACAAGAUAGCAGUCCUUUCCCCUCAUCAAUUCCACAUGCCUUCCAGAUCAACUUUAAUAGUUUGUACACAGCUCUUUGUGAACAGCAGACAUCUGAUCAAGCAACUCUCCUCUUGUAUACCUUGCUCCAUCAAAAUAGUAAUAUUAGAACAUACAUGUUGGCUCGCACAGAUAUGGAAAAUCUUGUUUUACCAAUUCUUGAGAUUCUGUAUCAUGUUGAAGAAAGGAAUUCACACCAUGUGUAUAUGGCCCUUAUAAUAUUGUUGAUCCUUACGGAAGAUGAUGGCUUCAACAGAUCCAUUCAUGAAGUGAUACUAAAAAAUAUUACUUGGUAUUCAGAACGAGUUUUAACUGAAAUCUCCUUGGGGAGUCUCCUGAUCCUGGUGGUAAUAAGAACCAUUCAAUACAACAUGACUAGGACACGAGACAAGUACCUUCACACAAAUUGUUUGGCAGCUUUAGCAAAUAUGUCGGCACAGUUUCGUUCUCUCCAUCAGUAUGCUGCCCAGAGGAUCAUCAGUUAUACCUGCCGCCACUUGCGGAGAUAUGUUUAUGUGUUGGACAAACUGUAUUUCCCCCACUCUCACUGUUCUACGCUUCAGCAUUGCUUCUCGACCCUCAGUGACAAUGGAGAGGAACUCUUGUCUUUAACUUGCUCUCACAUUCUCAGAUCCUAUGCUUCCAGUUUAUUUUCUUUGCUGUCUAAAAAACACAACAAAGUUCUGGAACAAGCCACACAGUCCUUGAGAGGUUCGCUGAGUUCUAAUGAUGUUCCUCUACCAGAUUAUGCACAAGACCUAAAUGUCAUUGAAGAAGUGAUUCGAAUGAUGUUAGAGAUCAUCAACUCCUGCCUGACAAAUUCCCUUCACCACAACCCAAACUUGGUAUACGCCCUGCUUUACAAACGCGAUCUCUUUGAACAAUUUCGAACUCAUCCUUCAUUUCAGGAUAUAAUGCAAAAUAUUGAUCUGGUGAUCUCCUUCUUUAGCUCAAGGUUGCUGCAAGCUGGAGCUGAGCUGUCAGUGGAACGGGUCCUGGAAAUCAUUAAGCAAGGCGUCGUUGCGCUGCCCAAAGACAGACUGAAGAAAUUUCCAGAAUUGAAAUUCAAAUAUGUGGAAGAGGAGCAGCCCGAGGAGUUUUUUAUCCCCUAUGUCUGGUCUCUUGUCUACAACUCAGCAGUCGGCCUGUACUGGAAUCCACAGGACAUCCAGCUGUUCACCAUGGAUUCCGACUGAGGGCAGGAUGCUCUCCCACCCGGACCCCUCCAGCCAAGCAGCCCUUCAAGUUCUUUUAUUUCUGGGUAACAGAAGUAGACAGACAGGUUACUUGGUGUAUCUUCUGUUAAAGAGGAUUGCACGAGUGUGUUUUCCUCACACACUUUGAUUUGGAGAAUUGGUGCUAGUUGGCAAUAGAUAACUCAGCGUAGAUAGUAUUGCAAAAAGGGGAGGAAAUACACAACAAUAAUAAAUGUAAAAACCUGCUAUUCAACAUGCAGUUUUAUUUCGAAGCCAAAAAUCUAGAGCUUUCCCAAGAUCCUGUUGCCUUAGGCACAUCACACUUCAACAGUGCACACUAUCCAACAGUGCACACUAUUCAACAGUGCACACUAUUCAAAAGCGUAGACUAUUUUUUUGCAUGUUCAAGAUAUUUGUUUUGGUCUUAUGUGUGUGUGAGAGAGAGAGAUUCCUUUGACAUUAAGGAGCAUCAAUGAGAAAAGAUGAUGAGGCAGGAAUUAAUAAAGAAAUGAAGUCGUGUGUGUUUGGUUGCCUGUCAGAGGGCACACAAUUUCAUAAACACCAUGCCUGGACAAUUUGAUAUUAAUAUUUAACACCUCUGCAUCUUUUCUUAAAAAAGAAUAUGGGCCAGAUACAGUGGCUCACAUUUGUAAUCCCAGCACUUUGGGGAGCCAAGUUAGCAGAAUCCCUUGAGCACAGGAAUCUGAAACCAGCUUGGGCAACAUAGUGAGAUCCCAUCUCUACAAAAAACUUAAAAAUUAGCCAGGCAUGAUGGCACAUUCCUGUAGUCCUAGCUACUCAGGAGGCUAAGGUAGGAGGAUUGCCUGAGCCCAGGAGUUCAAGGCUGCAGUGAGCUAAGAACGUGCCAGUACACUCCAGCCUGAGCCACAAAGUGAGACCCUGUCUCGCAAAAAAAAAAAAAGAAAGAAAAGAAAAAGAAAAUGGCUACUUCUCAUGAAGCCCAGAUUAACUUUUCUGUGAAUAUGGCCUGUGAACUGUUGCUGGAAUUAAAUUGGAGUCUAGCACAAAUUAAGUUAAUCUACUCUGUAUUAAUCAUUGGGAAAAAGAAAAGCUUCAUUUGAAAACAGUCUUUUUCCUUCACCCACACUAAUAGAAAAAGGAGAGUAAUUUGUUCAUACUGUAUUCCACGUGGGAUGAAAAGCAUGUUUUGCUCUUUGUUUCUGGGCCGGUGUGAUCCGUGUGUUGGUGCCUGAGCUGGAGGAAGGAGCUUCUUGCAGGGAAACAGCCACUGGGGCCACAUUGAGGGCCAGUUGGGACCUUCCUUUCCAGUCACACUCUGUGUCCUCACGGGCCCCUUCACAGUCUAGAUAAGGAGCCUAGUUUCAUUCUCAAAGAAAAAGUAUUUGGUCUUCAACAUAGAAAGCACAAAAGCCCAGACGAGACUGAGCACACUGUUCGAAUCCACUGCCAGCUCAUCUGUGUCAGGGCUGGCUUCUCCUGUCCUGUGUCCCAGGGCUGCAGGCCCGUGUUAUUUGAGUCCAUCAAAUCUUCCGAGGGCCUCGGAGGAACCAUUCUCAGUCACCCCAAGCUCUGUAAAAGGUCAAAACACUGGCAGCCUCUCAGUGCACCACUGUGUGGGCUCCACACGGGAAGGCCUGGCCAAGCUGUGCUCUUAGAGGCUGUCGAGGUAGGGCAGGAAGCUUCCCUAUCCUCGUCUGGAUGGAAUGAAACAGAGGUUCCCUAAGGCCAAGGGACUCGUGGAGCGCCCAUCCCGGGUGGGGUCCCAGAGGUGAGUGCAGCUUGCCUCCUGUCCCCAAGGGGCUUGUUCUGUCAGGCCUCCUCCAGUCACUGCUGGAGUGGGGACUCUGACUCCUGUGUUCACCUCAGAGCCCAUGUACAGGCUAGAGGUGAGGCUUGGCAACAACUUCUACUAAUACUUAGCUUUGUGGCAGAGCCAGUCUGAAGGAGGAGAAGCGCUCUCAGCCAGCAGGGGGAGUGAUGAUUAUCAUUUCAGGUAGCAAGGAUAUGUAUUUACUAUGUGGGGAAAUAAUUUGCAACUUUAAUUUGUUUCCAAAGCAUUUUGAUUGGCUUCCUUUUCCUUUAAACCAAAAAAUUGUUUAAAUGUUUAAGGGUCAUGUGGAACAGCUGAGCUUCUGGCAGGACCACAGAACUGUCCUCUGAGUCUGAGGGCUGGGCAGUGCCACAGGACAGUCCCUGGGCUGCAGGACUGUCAGUGCUUGUUGUGUGAGGAAAUGAGGCCCUUCAAAAACCCAGUCAUCUUGACAGAGGGCACACUCCCAAGGAAGGCCUGACUGGGGAAUCAUACAGCCUCUCCUCCAGGCCUCUGGGCUCACUGAGGUGCCCCCAGAACCCUGAUUGCCCUCCCCUCUUUCCCUUUUCUCAUUCAUCACACAGUAGAAGCACUCACUAGCUAACAGCUCAGCUGGGGCAGCAGCCUCCAUGGAGGCCUGCAAGUGAUGCUCCCAGUCCUGGUUCCCGCUCAGGAGGGAGGCCCCACCACGUGCAUCACUGCCUCAGCUCUGCAAAGUCACCAGAGGCUUCUUCCUGAUUUUUGUGAAAGAUUUAUUAUAUGGCAAUAAAUCUGAAUGAUAAACUUUCAUUAUACUUGCAUUAAUUUUGAGUAUUAGUUUGCUUAGAAAUUUUUACACGAAGUAAAAAUGUGUAAUGAUGCAACACAGGAUCAUCGUGUGUUCAGAUGGAAAUUGGCAUCUGAUUUUACCCCAGAUCUGAAGCUGUUACUGCAUUGUGUCAUUUUAUCAACAAAGACUUCUGCCACAAUAUUUACUUUUAAAAGAAUUUGUCCCUUUCAAUAGCAUCUUCCCUAUCAAGAGUUCAAGGCACUUUGCAGAAGAGCUUCAGAUUUCUAACUCUAGUUCCCACAGUCACCCGUUGAGGCUGGUGUCAUACAAUCUAUGAACAACAACCUUGCAGCAGGACUGCCACCAUUCAGCAGUGCAGACAACACAGCUCAAGGACAAAGACAGAGAAAGGAAAGAAGAGAAGGUCCCUGAAGGUGAAGCAUAGAAAGUACACUGCACACACAGUUCUCUCUGGAAGGAAAGCACAGGAGCUGGGAAGUAGACGAUAGAAAGUGGAAAGGACACAGGACCAGCAUCAGAACACUCAGCAACUUCCUAAGAGCUUGCUAAGGUACAUCCAAGAGAAAUAUUUAGUGAGGGAAACUUUUAAGCACUGGAAUUGUUAAUAUAUCAUACUUUAAGCAACAUUUCGUCCUUUAGAUUCCGGGAGCCAGGGUUUUGCAUUGGGUGGUAGAGCUCUCUGCAUAAUUGAGUCACCCUGUGCUUUUUUGCAGAGCCAUAAAUUUUUGGCACUUGCUGAUACUUCAUAGGCUGGAGUCUCUGCAAGGUCAACCCUUUGGGUCUCUUAAUUCUUUCCUAGGCACUAUCCUGCAAUAUCAGUAGUUGCCACUUGAUUUUAGGGACUGAUUAUUAGGCCUUCUGACUCCAAAUUCAGAACAAUUCCAGUGUCCUACAUCACCUCCUGGAGUCAAAGAGGUCAGUUUCUAUUCAGUGAUGAAGAGCUAAGCUAGCUAUGCAUAUGAAGAACUGAGAAGUAGAUUAUAACACACAAUCCACAGCAAAUAAUGCAUAUUUAUUUUGUAUGAAUUAAAGCAUAAAAUUUAAUCUCAUUAGCGUAUAGCUAUUCAGAGUUCCCACUCAAAGCAAGGGAGACUCACCAGUAGCCCCAAGACCCUUGGCCAGGUCAUACUCAACCCCUAAUCUAACUUCACAAGGCUGUCUAAAUGUCAGCUACUCAGACACAGCCUCUGGCAUUAGCAAAAUCCCCCAGAGGAAAAGCAGCCCCAUAGAACUGGACAAGUAAUACUUAACUAUCUUGUUGACUCUGGGGUCCUUCAAGCAAAUUUUAAAAAUAUUUUUACCAGAUUUCCAAGUUGUCCUUAGCUUGAGGGUUGGUCCUCCAUUACUGUCAUUGGACUAUCCCUCAUGGGUAGUGCAGUUCAACUUCUAAACCACCUCAGUACCUGAAUGUGGUCCGAGGUGAAACCAGAUUACUGAUGCCUUCAGGUGCCCAAUUGAAGCAAAUGGCAAAUUCUGUGGAGGAAGUAAACAUAACCCAAGGCCUCAAAUUAUUUCUGCAGUGUUGCAAUCAGAAAUACCCAGGUAUGGGAGAAGACCAGACAACAUUAAUUACUUGAAUUAAAACCAUUAGAGGAAAACACAGACAAUAGAAAUAUCCAAACAGACUCCAGAUAAAGUUGUCGCAGAAUUUAAAACAGCUAUGGUUACUGUGUUCAAAAAAAUGAGACGCAUGGUCAAGAAUUUCAACAGAGAGUUAGAAACUGUAAAAGGCGCAUUGGAAAUUCUAUAACUAAAGUACUGUAAUGAGAAGAACAGUGAACAGGUUUAAGAGCAGAUUAGAAAUAACUGAAAAGAGAAUGAGUAAGAUGAAAAAUUGAGGGUGAGGGGUGGGAGCAGGAAUUAUAUAGUAAAAAAAACAGAACAUGGAGAAUAGAGGGUAAGAGACUUAAAGGGUACAGUGAGCAUGUCUGACCUGCUCAGACAUGCAGGGUAGUUGGCAUCUCAAAAGAGUAGAAGAAAGGAAUAUUUAAACAAAUGGCUGAGAACUUUUCCAAAACUCAUGAAAGAUAUCACACCAAAAAUUCAAGAAUCCCUCCCACAAACUCCAAGUGGGAUAAAUAAAAACAACCCACACCUAGAAACAUCAUAGUAAAACUGUUGAAGACCAAAGAAAAAUAAUAUUUUAGACCUGCUGGGGUGGGAGAGGGAAUAUAACCAUUAAAGGAGCAAUAAUAUUAGACUGACAGCUCCUUCUCAGCAGAAACAAUGGAAGACAGUGAAAUACUGCCUUUUAUGGUUCUGAAAGAAAAUGACUGCCAACCUAAAAAUUUCUAAUCAGGGAAAAUAUCCUGCAAAAAUGAAGAGGAUAUGAAGACAUUUUUAGAGAAACAGCUAGAAGAAUUAAUCAGCACGCCUACCCUAAAGGAAAAUUUAAAAGGUGUUUUACAGGCAGAAGGAAAAUAAUCCCAAACGUAAGGACAGAGCCCUAGGAAAGAUUGAAGAGCAAUGAAAAUGACACAUAAAUAUUGACUACAUAAAACAAUAAUUAUGUCUUAUGGAGUUUUAAAUAUAUAGAGAAAUAAAAUGUAUGAAAAUGAAAGGAUUUAUGUGGGAAUUUUAAGUGUUCUAAGACACUUGGCAUCAUCCAAGAAGAGAGUAAAAAUUCAUUUAAUAUUAGUCUUUGAUAACUCAUGUAUGCAUGAUAAUAUUUGAGAUAUCAAUAAAAGUGUAUAGCUUUCCACAUAAUAAGAGAGAAUUCGAAUAAUCAAUUCAGUGGAAGAUUUAAGAAUUGCAAAAGAGUCUAAGAAAGAAGAAAAAGCAGAACAGGUGGAACAAAUAGAAAGCAAGAUAUUUGUGAUAAAUCCAUUAUUACACUAAAUGUAAAUGGACUAAUGCUCAAAUGUUGACAAAUAUUGUCAGCCUUGUUUUAAACCAUAUGCUAUUUACAAGAGACAUUUUUAGAACAUGAAUUUAGAAAUUUUGGAAGAAAAAGAUGGAGAAAUACAUACCCAGCAAACAGUAACCAUGAGGAAACUGGUGUAGAUAUAUUUAAGUAAACUUUAAGGCAAUAAUUUUUUUAAGAAAUAAAAGGGUCAAUUCAAUUACUAGAAAGAUAAUCUAAAUUUAUAUGCACUUAAAAUAUAAACUCAAAAUAUGUAAAAGAAAAUUUGAUAGGAAAUUUAGACAAAUAUGCAACCAGAGUGAUAUUUUAACAUGCCUAUUUUGUUAAUUGGUAGAAAAACUAGCAUACAAAAAUCAAGUUAUAAAAGAUUUAAGCAAUGAAAUGAGCAAACCAAACGGAUGUAUGUAGGACACCAAACUCAAUAACAUACUUUUCAAACACAAAUGGCACACACUCCAAAAUACUGGGCUAUAAAGGUUUCAACAGGCUAGGCACAGUGGCUCACAUCUGUAAUACUAGCACUUUGAGAGGCCAAGUCAGGAAGAUCACUUGAGCCCAGGAGUUUGAGACCAGCUUGGGCAACAUAAUGAGGCCCCACCUUUACAAAAAAUAAAAAAAUUAACUGGGCAUGGUGGCAUGUGCCUAUAGCCCCAGCUACUUGGGAAGCUGAGGCAGGAGAAUCACUUGUGCCCAGGAGGUCGAGGCUGCAGUGAGCUAUAAUUGCACUACUGCACUCCAGCUUGGGUGACAGAGCAAGACCCUGUCUCAGAAAAAAAGUCUCAACAAACCUGAAAAUACUUCAAAUGAAAUAUGUUCUCUGACCAUAAUAGAAUCAAGACUAAUUAUUUACAAAAAGAUAAUUUUAUAAUCCUCAUAUUUUUGGAAAUAGAUUUCCAGGUAACCCAUCUGUCAGAAUCUUAAUGGAAAUUUGAAAUAUUUUGAACUGAUCAUGAAAAUACUACAUAUCAAAACAGAGAAAAAACUUGUGGGAUGCAAAUAAAACUAUGCUUAGAAGACCUUUUAAUUUUAUUUUAAAUUUAAAGAGUACCUGUUCAGGUUUGUUACAAGAAUAUAUUGAUGAUGCUGAGGUUUGGGCUCCUAAUGAUCCUGUCACCCAGAUAGUGAACAUAGUACCCAAUAGAAAGUUUUUCAGCACUUGCUUCCCUCUCUCCUUCCCUUCCUCCCUCGUUUUGGAGUCCCUAGUGUCUAUUGUUCAUAUAUAUAUAUACACACACAUAUAUAUUUAAAUGUUUAUGUUAGAAAAGAAGAAAGGUUAAAAAUCAAUUAAGCAAUUACCUCAAAAAUUUUAAAAACAGCACAUGAAACCCAAAAAUAAGCCAAAUUACUGAUAUAGAACACAAAUAUACAAUAAAGGGAAUCAAAGUCAAAAGUUGGUUAUUUAAAAGGAUUAAGAGGACUCAUUGGCUGGGCAUGUUGGCUCACAUGUGUAAUCCCAGCACUUUGGGAGUCACCUGAGGUCAGGAGUUCAAGACCAGCCUGGCCAACAUGAUGAAACCCCGUCUCUACUAAAAAUACAAAAAUUAGCUGGGCGUGGUGGUGGGCAUCUGUAGUCCCAGCUACGCAGGAGGCUGAGGCAAGAGAAUUGCUUGAACCUGGGAGGUGGAGGGUUCAGUGGGCAGAGAUUGUGCCACUGCACUCCAGCCUGGGCAACAGAGCGAGACUCCGUCCCAAAAUAAAUAAAUAAAAGAAUUCAUAACCCCUUAAAAGACUGAUCAAAGAAGGAAGGAGAAAGGGCAGGAGAGAGGAAUAGCCAAUAUCAGAAAGGAAAACAGGUAAGUUACUUCAGAUUAUGCAGACAUUUAAAAUAUUUAAGAGCCAGCCUGGAUAACAUGGUGAAACCCUCCUGUCUCUACACACACACACACACAAAUUAGCUGAGCAUGGUGGUGUGUGCCUGUAGUCCCAGCUACUGGAGAGGCUAAGGUAGGAGGAUUACCUGAGCCCAGGAGGUAGAGGCUGCAGUGAGCUGUGGUCAUGGCACCACACUCCAGCCUGGGCAAUGGAGUGAGAGACCGUGUCUCAAAAAUAUGUAUACAUAUUUAAGAGAAUAUUAUGAAUACCAAUAAAUUUUAAAUCUAGUUGAAAUGAUCUUUAUUGCAGUGAUAGGUGUAUACAUAUGUCUAAUCAAAUUGUACACUUUAUUACAUAUGUGCAGUUUUAUAUAUUAAGUAUGCCUCAUUAAAGUUGUUUUUAGAUUUUGCA